GCUUCAGUAGCGAGAGGGGCUGAGAAAGUGGUGACACCGCCGGGGUGCGGAGGGAGUCCCUGAAACUUCUCCCAACAGCCCCAGGGCCAAUCUUCCCUCAGCCCACUCCCCUCUUCGCCAGCUCCCAGGUCCCCACUCCUGUACCGGGGGUGGGGUGGGGAGCCAGGCCCGUCUCCCGCUGGGACACACACAGGGGCCGGGAGCGGGGACGGGACCCCCGAGGCGGGGGGGACGAACCGACAGACAGACGGCUGGGCGCCCGCCCCAGCGGGCAGGCAGGCAGGAGGAGGCGGAGGCGGGGGUACGACGGGGAGCACUGGGUCUGGGGAGUUUCCUCUCAACUAUCGGGGGAGAAACUCCCCGCAGCCGGAGGAAAGACCCAGACAGUGUUUUCCUCCCGGGGGCCGUGCUCCCCCGCCCCGCGUAGCGGCGGUCGCCGCCACCGGCGCCUCCACCUCUACCAUCUCCUCUUUCUCCACCACCUCGGGCCCCGGUGUCCCCGGCCAGCACUAUGCCCAUCUUACUGUUCCUGAUAGACACGUCUGCCUCUAUGAACCAGCGCAGCCAUCUGGGCACCACCUACCUGGACACGGCCAAAGGCGCGGUAGAGACCUUCAUGAAGCUCCGUGCCCGGGACCCUGCCAGCAGAGGAGACAGGUAUAUGCUGGUCACUUUCGAAGAGCCGCCCUAUGCUAUCAAGGCUGGAUGGAAAGAAAACCAUGCAACGUUUAUGAAUGAAUUGAAAAACCUUCAGGCUGAAGGACUUACGACUCUUGGCCAAUCCCUAAGGACAGCUUUUGAUUUAUUAAAUUUAAAUAGAUUAGUAACUGGCAUAGACAACUAUGGGCAGGUAGGUUGAAUAAUAAGGUGGCAAAAUAGUUGAUUUUUCAUUUUGUGGAAAAACACAGUCCAGUCCAAAAACUACAUAACAUGAAAUGCAAGUAUAAAACAUUCCAAAUUAAAAUAGAAUAUGCACAUUGUUCAAAGGCAAAACUCUUACCCUACUAUAUAUAUUUUACAUCCCUCAUUUUUUCCCCCUCUAAAAUGCAUUGGUAUUCAGGAUUAGAAUCUGAAACUUUUGCUAUAAAGUUGACAUACAUUGGUUUUAAUCCCUUGAAAGUUCAGUAAAGACCUAAAAGGAAAAGCAUCCUACCACACCACACUCAUGUUGUAUGUGCAACUAUUAUAGUGGCUUAGAGACACUAGUUCGUGUUCUUCGUUUCUAUAUUAGUAAAGAUGUUAGAGGAAAUUAAUCUGUUUGUUGCAUCAGGGUUUAAUGUGACCAUGUUGUAUAACUAUUCUGAAAGGUAAGAAGUUUUUCACUGGAGUACAGUCACUGGCUGAGAACAUUUAAGUUUUCUUUUGAAGCAUACACAGUUAACAACUAUUGCAGGAAGAACUCUGAAUUAAAUUUCAGGCCCAGAGUUUUGAUUUAAACUCCAAACCCUUGGAAAAAAAGACUGCUGGAAAAUAUGAAAGAACCCUUCGUUUCUUAACCCCCACAAGUCCUUUUAUUGCACUUACUUUCAUGUAUUUGAGGAUGAGAGGAGCUUUAAAUCAACAAUAAUUCACUAAGGAAUAAUGCAAGGUGGUCUAUUGUAACAUUUUAUGAUAUUAUUGCCCUGGAAAUAAAAGAUACUGAACAAUGUAUAAUGUUACAUGUAACAAAGGAAUAUUAUUUCCAAGGAGCUCAGUUCUUAUGUUGUAGUGAAAAGCACUAUUCCUAAUUAUAUAUUGGGUAUAUGUUGUAUUUUCCCAAGUCCCACAGUCCCUAGUUUUGUGAGUUUCGUACAUUUCAGGGAAAUUCUUUCUGUGACUACAACUUUUAUUUGCUUCCUAUUGAAGGAAAUUGACUUGUUUCUGUUUUAGGAAAUUUUAAGCUUCUUAGGGAUAACUUCAGUGCUUAAGUGUCUUUGGAAAUAACUGAAUUUAGUUCUAUAACAUUUAAAAUGUACACUGAAAUUCAGAGUGAGCUUACCAAAUUGAACUUCCAACGUUUAGUUAGGUAAAUAUGUACUUUCUUACCACAUUAAUACUUUUAUGUUUUUCCCAUCUCUGCUGCUUUUAUUUUGCAACUUUUAAUAAUUUAGGUAGAUUUGCAAUGAACUUUUUGGUUUGUUUCUGUAAAAUAGUAGUGGAUUUCCUUCUCUUUUAUAUUCCUUUGUGAUAUGUAGUGCAACACAGUCUUACUGCUUAAGGUUUUCAUCCUUACCUCUUUGAGUUCAAAGAGAUAUUUAAAACUUGCCAUUAUUUGGUUACCUUUAUUUGGUUGUCAUGUUGUUAGUGUAUGGCAGAACUAUUAGUUUCCUCUUUUUCUGCAUCACAUUUCAUAAGUGGUCAAGGCAUUUGGACAUAUUCACCUCCUAUUACCUAUUAAAAAUACUUCUUAAAGAUUGCUUCCUUCGAAAAACUGCUUGUCAUGGAGAGGCUGAGGACAUUUGUAAUUUAAACCUGUAUUUUCCUUUUCCCAGUUGAUAUCUGCCCCCAGAGAACACUUUAGUUCUUGUCUAUAAGGCUUACCAAAAGUUUGCGGGAAAGGUGGUCCUGUGCUGUUACCACUUUGACCAAGAGAAGAACCUGGAGAUUGGGAUGUUUUUGCAUGUCAGGAUUUAUUAAUUCAAUAACAGAGAGGGAUGAUGCUUCUCACUUAUUCUGAUGAAUCAGCAAAGAUUGCAAAGCAUAAUAUUAAUGCUUAUGUCUUGAAUUGGCACAUUAAAAAUGACACUAGCAUUAAAAUAAGCCACUGUUUUCAAAUGAAAAUGAUAAUUUGAGUAAAGAGUAUUGAAUUGGAAGAAAACAUUCUUCCAGAAGAUUUUUUUCAUCAUAAAACUAUCUGAUUUAAACAUUUCAUGUUUUCUAUUCACAACAAGGAUAAAUGAUUAGGAAUUUUGGAUGUCUCAAAUAUUUAAUACUGAAUAUUGUUCAUGUGUUUUCUUCUUUGUAAAAGUACUUUGUAUCUGCCUGUUUGCUGUGGAAUACUUUUAUUUUGUAACUUCAAUGUCUUUACAUAAGUAUUUCCCCUUUCCUGCUCUAUACUAGGAUCUGUGGUGUUCACAGUACUAAAUACUUGUAUGUAACGUUAGUAGUUGAAGGAAAUGAGAAAAGAUUAGGUGGAAGAUAGAACGUAUAUAUUUUAUAGAACAUCUAAAAACUUUAAUGUUCUGAAUUACUUUCUUAAAUGUCUGGGUUAAUAUAUAUAUUUGUAUAUUUAUGUAGAUAUCCACCAUUCUCCCACAUAUAUGCACAUAUAUGAUUUUUCAUAACUAAUUACAAGACUAUUAAAUCUAUAUUGCAUUUGUUAACUUAGUUAACAUACCUACAGAUAAAACAUCUUUGAAUUAUUAGCUAGGAUGCUAUCAGAAUUUGCAGGGCAUUAGUAAGGUUAAGUAACUGAGAAAAAAGAAUGGUUCUUAGUGAAUGUUUUCCUCAAGCACUUUGGGUAUCCCACUAAAAAAUUCCAUGCCUACAGACAUUGUUAUAAAUAUUUAAUUUUGAUAAUCAGUACCAUUUACUGAUAUUUCUACAGUAAUGGAGCAAUGUAUAGCCUUUAGUCAAUCUUUUCCUUUAUAGCAGUACUUUAAGUUGCAUAUCAUUGCAGAUAAAUUUGAUACAUAAGUUUUUCACGUGUGUUCAACAGAGUUUCAAAUAAUGCUGAUCCUUUGAGACCUGCUGAAAGUCUGAAGCAGCCUUAAUAUCUAAAAUUAGGAAAUGUAUAAAAUGUGAGAGGUCUGAUUAAAGUUUUAUAUGUAGAUGAGUUAAUUUUCUUAUUGUUACAGGUCAUCCUGUUUUCCAUCAAUAUAUAUGUAUAUUUUUUUUGAGACAGAGUUUCUCUCUUGUUGCCGAGGCUGGAGUGCAGUGGCGCGAUCUCGGCUCACCGCAGCCUCCUCCUCCUGGGUUCAAGCCAUUCUCAUGCUUCAGCCUCCUGAGCAGCUGGGAUUACAGGCUUGAGCCACCAUGCCUGGUUAAUUUUGUAUUUUUAGUAGAGACUGGGUUUCUCUAUGUUGGUCAGGCUGGUCUCGAACUCCUGAACUCAGGUGAUCUGCCCACCUUGGCCUCCCAAAGUGCUAGGAUUACAGGCGUGAGCCACAGCACCCGGCCCGAUAUUUUCAACAUUGUCUUUUUUUUUUUUUUUUUUUUUUUUCAGUAAAUUAUGUUAGUUAAGAUUAGCCAAUAUAUCUUUACUCUGGCCUGCAAGUCCGUUUUUGUUACUGACCUGAUUCCACACCCCUGCUACCUGAAGUAUGUUAGUACUGAUUAAAUUGUUCCAGGAGUUAGAAUGGCACCUUUCCUACUAUGUGCCCUUGGUGAAGACAAUCCUUGACAGAUAUCUUAAAAGGAGAUAAAAUAUGUGCUUAAUUUUUUGAGGAUUUUCUAUGGUGAAUGUUUACCUCAUUGAAAAAUGGUGGCUUUCGUACAAUAUCAAAUUUAAUGAUUCUCAGGGAAAAGAAUUUUAACCAAUUUUAUUUUUGAGCAUAAAGGUCUAUUUUGUAAACUUAGGAGAUAAUACAGUUAUAGUUCUAAUACUACUUUUUUUUCCCUUUACCUAAAUAGUACCCAUUUAAUAGGUAGUGUGAAAUACAGGCUUCUUUUUGAAGGCUGGCAGGUGAAGUAGUGAGAACUCCAUUUCCAUUUGGGUGCUUGGUUUCUCUUAGAUUAUCAACAAAUGUAUGAAUAAGAGUUUGAUAUUUAUUAAGCUAUAGACAUCUUUUCAAAUGAAAGUAAGUUAAUUACUAUACCUGAAAUACUGCUGUGUUGAAUAUAAACUGGAAACACAAUGAUGAAUAGUAUUUUGUAAAUUUUUUAAUUCCUUUAAUUAAAAUUUUUUUUUAAAUUGUGGUAAGAAACACCUAACAAAAUUUACCAUCUUAACCAUCUUUAAGUGUGCAGUUCAGUAGUGUUAAGUAUAUUCAUAUUGCUGUGCAACCAAUAUCCAGAACUUUUUUAUCUUGCAAAAUUGAAACUCUAUAUCAAGUAACUCCCAGUCCCUGGAAACCUCUAUUCUACUUUCUGUUUUUAUGAAUUUGUCUACUCUGGAUAUCACAGUUAAGUGAAAUCAUACAGUAUUUGCCUUUUUAGAUGGGCUCAUUUCACUUAGCAUAAUGUUCUCAACAUUCAUUUAUAUUUUAGCAUGUCAGGAUUUUUUCAUCCUUUUUAAGGCUGAAUAAUACUCUAUUGUAUGUACCACAUUUUGCUUAUCCACAUAUCCAUUGAUAGUCACUUGGGUUGCUUCCACUUCUUGGCUGUUGUGAAUAAUGCUGCAAUGAACAUGGUUGUGUAAGUAACUUUUUGAGAUCCUGCUUCCAGUUCUUUUGGAUAUAUACCCUGAAAUGAAAUGACAGGAUCAUAUUGUAAUUCCAUUUUAAAUUUUUUGAGGAAGUACCAUACUGUUUUUCAUAGCAGUUGUACCAUUUUACGUUCCUACCAACAGUGCACGAGGGUUACACUUUCUUUAUAUCUUCACUAACACAAUUUUCUGUUUUACUUUGACAUUAGCCAUCCUAUUGGGUGUGAGGUCGUAUCUCAUUGUGGUUUUUAUUUACAUUUUCCUAAUAAUUAUUUAUGUUAAGCAUCAACAUACGCUUGUUGGCCAUUUGUACACUGUCUUUCGAGAAAUGUUCAUUCAAGUCCUUUGCCCGUUUUAAAAUUGUUUUUUGUUGUUGAGCUUUAGGAUUUCUUUAUAUUUUCUGGAUAUUAAUCCCUUAUCAGAUAAAUGAUUUGCAAAUAUUUUCUCCCAUUAUGUAGUUUGCUUUUAUACUCUGUUGUUUCUUCAGUGCACAAAAUUUUUAUUUUUGUAUGGUCCAGUUACAUAUUUUUACUUUUAUUGCCUGUGCCUUUGGUGUCAUCCACAAAAUCAUUGCUAAAUCCAAUGUCACUGAAGCUUUUCUCCUGUGUUUUAAGAGUUUUAUAGCUUUAGAUCUUCUGUUUAGAUCUUUAAUCUAUUUUGAAUUAAUUUUUGUAUAUGGUAUAAGGUAAGGGUCCAACUUCAUUCUUUUGCAUGUGGAUAUCCAGUUUUUCCACCACCAUGUUGAAGAGACUUGCCCUUUCCCAUUUGAAUGGUCUCUGCAAAUCCCUGAACUUUUGAGCCUCAAUAAUUUUUGUUGGUGGAGAGGGCACUCUCCUGUCAAACUUGCUUAAAUGUUUUUUCCCCAUCUUUAUUGUGUAAAAGAAGAGCAGUGGCUAGAAAUGUGAGAAUUGGAAUCCCAAUCUUGGCCUCGCCAUUGAAUUAUUAUGUAACAUUGAGCAUUCACAUUACUAUUUUGAGCCUCUGCUACUUCUUAUUCCAAGUUGGCAAUAAUGAAGCCAUUGUACCUUUAAUAUAGAAUUGUUGAGAGGUUUAAAUGGGAUGAUAUAUUUAAAAUGUACCUUAUUAGGAUGUCUCACUAGACAAAAGCAUCCUUUUCCUCCAAAAGAUUAGUAUGUUUACCUCUAGUUUUCUAUUUUUUUCAGCUUUAAUUUUGAAAUUAAAAUUAUAAAAAUCUUCAAAGCUGAUUAUUACAUGCUUUAAACAUCUAUUAGUAUCACGAAGUAUAUGUUUUUCUUUGGGCUUUGUAUUGUAUCCCAGAAAAGCAGGUGUGAAAGAAAAUUAAUAUAACUUGGCCAAAGUUGUCUCAGUGGCAUUUAAUAAGCAUAGGAUGAUGUUUUUAAAGAAGUGUUAAAACAAUUUAAAUAAUUUAGCAGAUAAGUCAGAAAGUCAUUCUUUUGCAAGAAUACUUAUGUGAAAAAAGCACAUGCCUUAGGAUUCUUUCAAAUAGGGAGCUCCCCCUAGUGCGUUUUAGAUGAGAUUUACACAAGUUUGAUUUGCAGGGAACCUUUUAGGAGCACAUAUGUUGGGUAAAUCAAGGGAUAGUUUAAUAAGAUUUAACUGAGCUCAAAGUAGUACAAAAUGGAUAUGAUUUAUUUCCUAUAGAGCAUUAAUUUAAUGGUGGUAUAAUUUAAAUGAGAAGGAAUAUCCCCAAACCCAGAUUUUAUUUUCUUUUAAAACAUUUGCAAAAUAUUUCUUCAGAAUUUUAUACUCUAAAACUGUUUUCUAAAAGAAAAAAUUCUCCAGUCAUGAUCUGAAAAAAAAAAAAAAAAGAAAAAUGAAAAACACUAUCCUAAGGAUGUUAUUGCAUUCUUUUUUUUUUUGGGAUAGAGUUUCACUCUUGUUGCCCAGGCUGGAGUGCAAUGGCGUGAUCUUGGCUCACUGCAACCUCUGCCUCCCGGGUUCAAGCCAUUCUCCUGCUUCAGCCUCCUGAGUAGCUGGGAUUACAGGCUCCCGCCACCACCCUCGGCUAAUUUUUGUAUUUUUGGUAGAGACGGGGUUUCGCCAUGUUGGCCAGGCUGGUCUGAAACUCCUGACCUCAGGUGAUCCGCCCACCUCGGCCUCCCAAAGUGCUGGGAUUUACAGGCGUGAGCCACCGCCCCUGGCCAUUAUUGCAUUCUUAAUUAGAAAUUGUUCAAAACAAAUCUUAAAUACAAAAGUCAAAAAUAGGCCGGGUGCCAUGGCUCACACCUGUAAUCCCAACACUUUGGGAGGCUAAAGCAGGUGGAUCACUUGAGGUCAGGAGUUUGAGACCAGCCUAGACAAUGUGGUGAAACCCCAUCUCUACUAAAAAAAAAAAAAAAAAAAAAAAAAAAAAAAAUUAGCUGGGGGGUGGUGGCAUGUGCCUGUAGUCCUAGCUACUCAGGACUCCUGGAGUCCUGGUUGGAGGAUUGCUUGAACCCCGGAGGUGGAGGUUGCAGUGAGCUGAGAUGGUGCCACUGCACUCCAACUUGGGCAAUAGGCUGUCUCAAAAAAACAAAACAAAACAAAAACAAACAAAAAACCAAAUAAUAUAUUCUACUUUAAAGAGCAUUUUACUUUCUUUCGAUAUAGGAGAAUAUCGAUAAUUAUGUAUUAUAUACAGCUGGAAAUUAAAAGAUCAGGAACAAAUCUAAUAUUUGACAUCAUUGGACUUAUUUGUGUAUUUUGAAUUAAGGUCAUUUGUGGUCAAAAUUAGUUAAAAGGAUUGUUUAUUUAGUCAUGUUCAUGUCAUAGAUUUCUACAAAGAGAUUAUAUAGUAUUUUAUAGCUUGAAAUGUUUCUCAAAUAUAUAAAAUGAUUUUUGGCCAUAAUAACCUUGACUCAGAUUUAUACUCUACAAUUAAAUUAGUCUUGGUGGACUUUUCUUGUUUUUUGGGGCUUUUUAAUUUUAAAAAUGUUUAGAUACAAAGUCUCUCUGUGUUACCCAGGCUGGUCUUGAACUCCUGGGCUCAAGCAGUCUUUCCACCACGCCUUCGGAGUAGCUGGGACUGCAGGCUCUUGCCAUUGUACUCAGCUUAAAAAAGUAAUUUCCUUAUAUAAACUUUAUUUUUGUUUAGUCUUACUAUUAGUCUAUAAAAGUUUACCAUGGUUGCCAGACUUUAAACAAAAUACUAAAUUUUUAAAAAAUUUUGUUUUGGUUUGUAUUUUCUGAUCUCUAACAUUUUUAUUGAGAUGUAACUUAAAUAAACAAAUCUGAAGUGUGAAGCUUAGUGAAUUUUAAAAUAUACACUCUUAAAAAAAUUGAACAUUUGCAUCUACUGACAAGUUUUCAUUAAACUUUCUGUGUUUUAUUAUUAUUUUCAUAGGGCUUUAGAAUGGAAGUGAUUUUAGAAGUUUACUCAAUUUUCCUCAUUUUGUAGGUGAAGAAAAGGCAUAGAAAGGUUCAGAGGCUUAAUUUCUUCACAUUUAUGAAAUAUUUUUAAAAAUUGUAAUUGGUGAUAGAACAGUUAUGGAGAUUUUAUUAAGGAUUUGUAUAUUAUUUAAUAACAUUUUAUUUAAAUGUAUAAGCAGUGGAUCUGAGUUGCUUUCUUCAGUUUUGUGUAUAGUUCUGUAAUGCAGUAUGAUUUCUUUCAGUUCUUGUUUGAAAGCUAAGCUUUUCAUUUUGUCUCUGUUACAUUUAGUCUUUCUUGUAACAUUCUAUCUAAAUACUGUUUGUUACAAAAUUAGCUUUAGUUGGAUUCCUUCCUCCCUUUGUUUGGCAGAAAGUAAAUGAAUUUAGGGCAGCGGUCCCCAGCCUCUUUGGCACCAGGCUGGUUUUGUGGAAGACAGUUUUUCCAUGGAUUGGUAGAGGUGGUUGGGAUGGUUUCAGAUGAAACUUUUCCACCUCAGGUCAUCAGGCGUUAGAGUCUCAUAGGAGCGCAUAACCUAGACCCCUUGCAUGCACAGUUCACAACAGGGUUUGUGCUCCUAUGAGAAUCUAAUGCUGCUGCUGAUCUAACAGGAGGCGGAGCCCCAACGGUAAUGCUCACUUGCCCACUGCUCACCUUCUGCUGUGCCACCCAUUCCUGAUGGGGUCCAGGGGUUGGGGACCCCGAUCUAGGGGAUAAACCAGGAAAGACUUCUUAGAGGUAGUAGCAUCUGAAGAAUAAAAGUUUACUGAGAACCCAGAACCCUUGCAGGUUAGGGGGCAAUGCAGAGUGAAGAUCAUGAUCAAUGGCCAGAUGCGAUGGUUCAUGCCUAGUAAUCCCAGCACUUUGGGAGGCUGAGGUGGGUGGAUCACCUGAGGUCAGAUGUUCGAGACCAGCCUGGCCAACAUGGUGAAACUAAAAAUACAAAAAUUAGCUGGGCAUGGUGGCGGGCGCCUGUAAUCCCAGCUACAGGCACCCUCAGGAAGCUGAGGCAGGAAAAUCGCUUGAACCCAGGAGGCAAAGGUUGCAGUGAGCUGAGAUUGCGCCAUUGCACUCCAGCCUGGGCGACAAGAACGAAACUUCAUCUCAAAAAAAAAAAAAAAUCAUGGUCAAAAACAUAGGAGAGGCUGUCCCUGUGGCUCACACCUGUAAUCCCAGCACUUUGGGAGGUUGAAGAGGGAGGAUCACUAGAGGCCAGGAGUUCAAGACCAGCCUGGCCAACCUGGUAAAACUCCAUCUCUGCCAAAAACACAAAUAUUAGCCAGGCAUGGUGGUGCACGCCUGCAAUCCCAGCUACUCAGGUGGCUGAGGCAGGAGAGUCACUUGAACCUAGGAGGUGGAGGUUGCUGUGAGCCAAGAUUGUGCGACUGCACUCCAGCCUGGGUGACAGAGUGGGAAUCUGUCUCAAAAAAAAAAAAAAGGCUGGAGGUGGGGAGGCCUGGGGACGUAUGGGAUAGUUGACAGGAUUUUAUACUGUAAUUACUUUAAGGCCUAGAUUCUAAUAACAUACAUAAGUAUUUAAUGGCACUUUUUGGUUUUGUGCUUCAUACUUUAAGUUUCUGAUGUGUAGCUAGUUAAUAUAGAGCUAUUAACCUUGUUCAUUAGUCAAUUUUUCCAAUGUAGUAUGCCAACCAGUAUUAGGGUUACAUUUAUAACUUUUUUCCUGGAGAGUUGAUGAGUUAACUACCAUAUUUUCAUUUAACUUAAGGUAGUUUUGAAAAUUUCUAAGCAUUAUAUCUUAAGAUUCAGAAAAAUAAGACCAGAUCCACUUAUGAAUUUCCAUUCCACUCGUGACCUGACAAGUCGUAUAACCUCUCAGCCUCACUUUCCCCAUUAGACAAAUAGAAUGAAAAGACCUAUCUUGCAGAACUGUGAUAAAGAUUAAGGAAUGUACAACAUAAUUUAUUAUUGUAACACAACCUAUUAAUCAUUUUUAUGUAUUUUCUCUUAUUUGAAUUUUAAAAAUUGAAAUUAUGGGGUACUAGAGGUUUUUUUAAUCUUGCUUUUUUCAGAACAAGCAGCAUGGUGGUAUGGAAAGAACUGCUGUAUUAGAACUGGCUGUGCCUGGUUCUGUCACUCACUAGCUUAUAUUGUAUUGAAAAGUCCCUUAAUCUCUCUGAGCAUCAAGUUUCUCAUCCAUAGAAUUGUGAUUAUACCAAUGCUUAAAUUUUGUGAGGAUUAGAAGUAAUAUUUGUUAAUCAUCUAGCAAAAGUGCCUGCCUGGCAUAUGGUAGGGGCUCAUUUAUGAUGAUGAUCAUCAUCUCCAGUAUUACGGUAAACACUUAACAGGAUAAAAGCUUUUUAGUCUGAAACCUUUGACAAAAACAGAAUUAAGGUUGUUCCAUAACCUAUCAUACAGUUAUGUAUCGCUUAACAAUGGAGAUAGGUUCUGAGAACUGCACCAUUAGGCAGAUCUGUUGUGGGAACAUCAUAGAGUAUACCUACAGAAACCUAGAUGGGAUAGAUGACUAUACCCCUAGGCUAUAUGGUAUAUGACCCAUUGCUCCUAGGCUAUACAUCUACCUGUAUAGCAUGUAACUGUACUGAUUGCUCUAGGCAGUUUUAACACUUACAAGCAUUCAUGUGUCUAAACAGAUAUAAACAUUGACAAAUACAGUAGAAAUAUGGUAUGAAAGAUAAAAAAUGGUAUACCUAGAUAGGGCACUUACCAUGAAUGUAGCUUGAGGACUGGCAGUUGCUCUGGGUGGGUGAGUGAGUUCGUGAUGAGUGAAGUGAAGGCCUGGGACAGUACACUGCUGUAGACUUUAUAAACUGUACACUUAGGCUACACUAAAUUUAUUAAAAAAUUUUCUCCAAUAAUAAAUUAACCUUAGCUUACUGUAACUUUAUAAACUUCUAAAGUUUUAAAACUUUUUAACUCUUUUUAGUAAGAUUUAAGAUACAAACAUAGCUGUAUAAAAUAUUUAUAUCCUUAUUCUGUAAGCUUUUUUCUAUUUUUAAAAUUGUUAUUUUUUUAAAAACUUUUUUUUUUUUUGAGAUGGAGUCUUGCUAUGUCACCCAGGCUGGAGUGCAGUGGCUCGAUCUCUGCUUACUGCAAGCUCUGCCUCCUGGGUUCACGCCAUUCUCCCGCCUCAGCCUCCUGAGUAUCUGGGACUACUGCCACCACACCUGGCUAAUUUUGGUGGUUUUUUUGUAUUUUUAGUAGAGACGGGGUUUCACCGUCUUAGCCAUCAUGCUCUCCUGACCUCCUGAUCUCCUGACCUCAUGAUCCGCCCGCCUCGGCCUCCCAAAGUGCUGGGAUUACAGACGUUAGCCACUGCACUGGCCUUUGUUAAAAACUAAGACUUACACUCAUUUUUCUAGGCGCACACAGGGUCAGGAUCAUUAAGAUGUCAGGAGGUGAUAGGAAUUUUUCAGCUGUAUUAUAAUCCUACAGGACCACUGUCAUGUAUAUGGUGGUCUGUCAUUGGCCAAAACAUUAUGUGAUGUCUUACUGUACAUCCAUCAUGAGAAGCCAUAAGUAGCUAUCCAGUUUUUUCUGGCUAAAGUAAUUUUCAAAGCAAGAAAGGUUUUAAACUUCUUUGAGAAAAUUUAGAGUUUAUUUCUAGGACUUUGUAUAUUUUAGAAUUCACGUUGGUGAUGGUUGGGAUGGGGGUUUAGGGGAGGUGCUCUCCUCCAGAAGAAAAGUCAAGUGUAAAAUAUAUAAUUCCUUUUAUUUGUCGUGUAGAUUUGUGUAGGAAAAGACAUAAUAGGAUAGGCCUAGGAAGAAUUUUUUUAUAUGAAGAUUUUUUUUUGAAGGGCAUAUAUAAUUGGAAAUUGAUUAUUGGUAUAUGGAGAGAGAGAAUUGUACAUGAAAAGUACUAUAACUUAAAAAACCUUACAGUUAAGAGGAUUAGUUGUAACCAAAGGACAAAUUUAUGUCAGUCUAGUGAUUAGUCCUAUCAAAAAUUAUUCUAGCUUUCAUAUAACCUGUUUUUUAUUGCCUGUUUUAUCUGUGACAUGUUGACAUCUUCCUUCUAUUAGUUUUUGCCCAAAUGAGGUGUGGGACUCCUAGUGAAGGUCCUUGGAAGGAUUAUAUUUUCUAUAAAACUUUAUUAGGGACAUGAUAACAGUUCUGAAUAUGUGAGAAAAAGUAAUUGUAUACUAUUAGGUGAUGCAGUUUGUAGCUAGGAAAUGACAGAGUUGAUGCUGGUGUGUCAGAGUAAAACUUUCCCUUUGUCUUAAAGCGAGUGAACCUUGUUAGGUACUAGGAAACAACAACAGUCUUUUGGUUAUUCUGGGGUUUCAACACUGGAAAUAUCUAAUAACAGAAUUAUUCUGAAAUAAUUGAAAACUAUUUUAAAUAAGGAAUUGAAGAUAAUUGAAUAUGCAGUGUGAAAGGUCAGGCUGCAAGUGACAGUGGGUGAUGUUGCAAGACAAUGACAAGGUACAGUGCUUUUGGAUUAUCAGGAAUUAGCAAAAUGAUGUCUUGGUGUCCUCUGGUAAUUUCUGAGUUGUGAACUAUCUUGCUUAUUUAUAUACUUUGGCAGGUAAUGAAAUAAUGAAUGUAAAAUUUUGAAUUUUGUGUAAUCACAUUUCUUAAACCAAUAAGUUAGAAAGGAAAACCAAGAGAUUGCAUCCACAAGAUCAGGCCUAAAUAGGUAGUAGAAAGAAUAGAAGGUCUUUAUUUUAAAUUUUAUUUUUAAUUCAGAAUGGGCAGUGUCUAAUCACAAAUGAGAUUAUAGUGAAUGUAAAUCUUAAUGUAACAAAGGAUUAUCUUGCCAUGUUCUUAAAGUUUCCAUUUUAAUGAGCUUUAGUAACAUUCUAAAACAUGUAGCAAUCUGUGCAGUCAUCCGUAUGUGACAUCUGCUUCUUCAUGAAGUGCAUUUCUAAGGUAAAACUAUUGGUUUAUUUGUAUGUAUAGUUAGGAAGGCUUAUAAAACUUUUUUUUUUUUAAUGAUAGGCACAAGUAUUAUGUAGUUAGAUUUUUUUUGUUUCUGGAAAAUGUUAUCUACUUUGAAAAUUUUAAAUCUAUAAACACUUGGGAAGGUGUUUAGCACAAGCAUCAAUAAAUGUUUCAAUCAGAAUCUAGCAAGAAAGGAUUCUUAGAAACUUUUACUCCUGUACAUGUACUGUGUAAUGGAUUUAGAGAAAUUUGUUUCCUCCUAAAAAAUCUUAGCAAUGUUGGGUUAGUACCAUUUCUUUCCUUGAAAACAAAAAAAUCCACAUUUUUUACGAACCAGGGCCCCUUAAAACUAAUCUCACAUUAUGUCUUUUUUUUAAUUAUUAUUGUUUUUGAGACACAGUCUUGCUCUAUCGCCCAGGCUAGAGGGCAGUGGCAUGAUCUUGGCUUACUGUAAUCUCUGCCUCCCAGGUUCAAACAAUUCUUGUGCCUCAGCCUUCCCAGUAGCUGGGAUUACAGGCAAGUGCCACCACACCUGACUAAUUUUUGUAUUUUUAGUAGAGACAGUGUUUCAACAUGUUGGCCAGGCUGGUCUGGAACUCCUGACCUCAAGUGAUCCUUCUGCCUCAGCCUCCCAAAGUGUUGGAUUACAGGUGUGAGCCAUCACGCCCGGCCUCACAUUAUGCCUUACCCAAUUAUUUUCAGAUUGGCCUUCAGCCAUAGCAUAUGGGAAACAAUAUACUGUUAGAGUUUUCCAAGUGCUUUUCAUGAAUUUUUUUUCCCUUUUUAAAAUUUAAUGCUUUAUUGCUAACUUUCCUGAUCUGAAACAUUUAUUAGGCAGUUCUUCAUUUUCAGUUGUAGCCUUUAAGAUAUUUAUAUAGAAGGCUGUCAUAGAAUGCCAUCUUCUUUUGUAGGACAGUUGUGUGUGUGAAUUGAUUUUUUUUUUUUGAGACCAUAUUUGUAGUGUGAUGUGUAGAAGGAAGUAACCAGAAUGGUUUUAUCUGCUUCUUUGCCCUACAUUCAAGGUCUGCUUGUGAUAGUAUUUAAAAUUGAGUUCAGUGCUGAGUUCAAGAUGGGAUUUAACCAGACUUUUACAAAGGUAGCAUCUGUAGAUUUUGUAGCAGUCUACUCAAGGAGGUGAUUAAUCUUGAGAGACUAGACAGAUUUCUUUUAGGUCAAAUUAAAUUUUACCAUUAUUGCUGUAUAACUCCAUUCACCUAUCUUUGAAAAUAUGUUUACAUCUUGGUUUUUAUUUAUACGUUUAUUUUUAAAAAACAUAUUUCUAACAUGUUUUUUAUUACAUGCUUCACUAGAAUAAAAUUUUCCCAAGUUAUUAUUACCCAGUUUAUCCUGAAAUCUUAGCCUCAGGCAGUCCUCCCACCUCGGUCUCCCAAAGUGCUAGGAUUACAAGUGUGAGCCACCGUGCCUGGCCCCAGUCCAUCUAAUGUAUGUAUUAGAUUCUUAGAAUAUUACUAUUUAUUAAGUAAAGUUAUAUUUCUGAUAGCUUAAUUACUCCUUAUAUGACAGCAUAAACACUAUUUGCCUGGCACUACUUUUUAGGCAUUCCCCAGACCAGUUUGUUAAUUUCAUUCAAACUUUAGAUUCCAGUUCAAGUAUAAAACUCAAAUUCUGCCAAAUUAUUAAUAUUUCAGAUAUAUUGAGUUUAUAUUAUCGUCUUUUGUAGUUAUACUUAGUCUUAUCAAUUAUUGAAUUUCCCUAAUGUUAUUAUUAUUUUUUUUUACAAAGUCAAACUUUAGUGAUUCUGCAGUUCUUAUGGUGACUUACGAUUUCUUACAUUAUUACUCUUCAGUCUAUUAUUAAAUCAAAUUCCAGGAUGGAGUUCCUUAGUCGUUACAUUAAAACAGAUAUAUGGAACUCCCCCCUACUUUUGCUUAAGUCAUAGUAUUCCAUCUGUUUUUAAUGCUGUUGUAUUUUUAACAUAAGGAAUUACGUGGUUGAAUAAAGGAAUUGUAUCGGAA